AGAGGGCGCUGCACACUCGCGCCCGAGGACUGCCUGCCCCCCUUCAGCCCCUCUCCCGGGCUGCGCCUCCGCACUCCGGGCCCGGGCAGAAGGGGGUGCGCCUCGGCCCCACCACCCAGGGAGCAGCCGAGCUGAAAGGCCGGGAACCGCGGCUUGCGGGGACCACAGCUCCCGAAAGCGACGUUCGGCCACCGGAGGAGCGGGAGCCAAGCAGGCGGAGCUCGGCGGGAGAGGUGCGGGCCGAAUCCGAGCCGAGCGGAGAGGAAUCCGGCAGUAGAGAGCGGACUCCAGCCGGCGGACCCUGCAGCCCUCGCCUGGGACAGCGGCGCGCUGGGCAGGCGCCCAAGAGAGCAUCGAGCAGCGGAACCCGCGAAGCCGGCCCGCAGCCGCGACCCGCGCAGCCUGCCGCUCUCCCGCCGCCGGUCCGGGCAGCAUGAGGCGCGCGGCGCUCUGGCUCUGGCUGUGCGCGCUGGCGCUGAGCCUGCAGCCGGCCCUGCCGCAAAUUGUGGCUACUAAUUUGCCCCCUGAAGAUCAAGAUGGCUCUGGGGAUGACUCUGACAACUUCUCCGGCUCAGGUGCAGGUGCUUUGCAAGAUAUCACCUUGUCACAGCAGACCCCCUCCACUUGGAAGGACACGCAGCUCCUGACGGCUAUUCCCACGUCUCCAGAACCCACCGGCCUGGAGGCUACAGCUGCCUCCACCUCCACCCUGCCGGCUGGAGAGGGGCCCAAGGAGGGAGAGGCUGUAGUCCUGCCAGAAGUGGAGCCUGGCCUCACCGCCCGGGAGCAGGAGGCCACCCCCCGACCCAGGGAGACCACACAGCUCCCGACCACUCAUCUGGCCUCAACGACCACAGCCACCACGGCCCAGGAGCCCGCCACCUCCCACCCCCACAGGGACAUGCAGCCUGGCCACCAUGAGACCUCAACCCCUGCAGGACCCAGCCAAGCUGACCUUCACACUCCCCACACAGAGGAUGGAGGUCCUUCUGCCACCGAGAGGGCUGCUGAGGAUGGAGCCUCCAGUCAGCUCCCAGCAGCAGAGGGCUCUGGGGAGCAGGACUUCACCUUUGAAACCUCGGGGGAGAAUACGGCUGUAGUGGCCGUGGAGCCUGACCGCCGGAACCAGUCCCCAGUGGAUCAGGGGGCCACGGGGGCCUCACAGGGCCUCCUGGACAGGAAAGAGGUGCUGGGAGGGGUCAUUGCCGGAGGCCUCGUGGGGCUCAUCUUUGCUGUGUGCCUGGUGGGUUUCAUGCUGUACCGCAUGAAGAAGAAGGACGAAGGCAGCUACUCCUUGGAGGAGCCGAAACAAGCCAACGGCGGGGCCUACCAGAAGCCCACCAAACAGGAGGAAUUCUAUGCCUGACGCGGGAGCCAUGCGCCCCCUCCGCCCUGCCACUCACUAGGCCCCCACUUGCCUCUUCCUUGAAGAACUGCAGGCCCUGGCCUCCCCUGCCACCAGGCCACCUCCCCAGCAUUCCAGCCCCUCUGGUCGCUCCUGCCCACGGAGUCGUGGGGUGUGCUGGGAGCUCCACUCUGCUUCUCUGACUUCUGCCUGGAGACUUAGGGCACCAGGGGUUUCUCGCAUAGGACCUUUCCACCACAGCCAGCACCUGGCAUCGCACCAUUCUGACUCGGUUUCUCCAAACUGAAGCAGCCUCUCCCCAGGUCCAGCUCUGGAGGGGAGGGGGAUCCGACUGCUUUGGACCUAAAUGGCCUCAUGUGGCUGGAAGAUCCUGCGGGUGGGGCUUGGGGCUCACACACCUGUAGCACUUACUGGUAGGACCAAGCAUCUUGGGGGGGUGGCCGCUGAGUGGCAGGGGACAGGAGUCCACUUUGUUUCGUGGGGAGGUCUAAUCUAGAUAUCGACUUGUUUUUGCACAUGUUUCCUCUAGUUCUUUGUUCAUAGCCCAGUAGACCUUGUUACUUCUGAGGUAAGUUAAGUAAGUUGAUUCGGUAUCCCCCCAUCUUGCUUCCCUAAUCUAUGGUCGGGAGACAGCAUCAGGGUUAAGAAGACUUUUUUUUUUUUUUUUUAAACUAGGAGAACCAAAUCUGGAAGCCAAAAUGUAGGCUUAGUUUGUGUGUUGUCUCUUGAGUUUGUCGCUCAUGUGUGCAACAGGGUAUGGACUAUCUGUCUGGUGGCCCCGUUUCUGGUGGUCUGUUGGCAGGCUGGCCAGUCCAGGCUGCCGUGGGGCCGCCGCCUCUUUCAAGCAGUCGUGCCUGUGUCCAUGCGCUCAGGGCCAUGCUGAGGCCUGGGCCGCUGCCACGUUGGAGAAGCCCGUGUGAGAAGUGAAUGCUGGGACUCAGCCUUCAGACAGAGAGGACUGUAGGGAGGGCGGCAGGGGCCUGGAGAUCCUCCUGCAGACCACGCCCGUCCUGCCUGUGGCGCCGUCUCCAGGGGCUGCUUCCUCCUGGAAAUUGACGAGGGGUGUCUUGGGCAGAGCUGGCUCUGAGCGCCUCCAUCCAAGGCCAGGUUCUCCGUUAGCUCCUGUGGCCCCACCCUGGGCCCUGGGCUGGAAUCAGGAAUAUUUUCCAAAGAGUGAUAGUCUUUUGCUUUUGGCAAAACUCUACUUAAUCCAAUGGGUUUUUCCCUGUACAGUAGAUUUUCCAAAUGUAAUAAACUUUAAUAUAAAGUAGUCCUGUGAAUGCCACUGCCUUCGCUUCUUGCCUCUGUGCUGUGUGUGACGUGACCGGACUUUUCUGCAAACACCAACAUGUUGGGAAACUUGGCUCGAAUCUCUGUGCCUUCGUCUUUCCCAUGGGGAGGGAUUCUGGUUCCAGGGUCCCUCUGUGUAUUUGCUUUUUUGUUUUGGCUGAAAUUCUCCUGGAGGUCGGUAGGUUCAGCCAAGGUUUUAUAAGGCUGAUGUCAAUUUCUGUGUUGCCAAGCUCCAAGCCCCAUCUUCUAAAUGGCAAAGGAAGGUGGAUGGCCCCAGCACAGCUUGACCUGAGGCUGUGGUCACAGCGGAGGUGUGGAGCCGAGGCCUACCCCGCAGACACCUUGGACAUCCUCCUCCCACCCGGCUGCAGAGGCCAGAGGCCCCCAGCCCAGGGCUCCUGCACUUACUUGCUUAUUUGACAACGUUUCAGCGACUCCGUUGGCCACUCCGAGAGGUGGGCCAGUCUGUGGAUCAGAGAUGCACCACCAAGCCAAGGGAACCUGUGUCCGGUAUUCGAUACUGCGACUUUCUGCCUGGAGUGUAUGACUGCACAUGACUCGGGGGUGGGGAAAGGGGUCGGCUGACCAUGCUCAUCUGCUGGUCCGUGGGACGGUGCCCAAGCCAGAGGCUGGGUUCAUUUGUGUAACGACAAUAAACGGUACUUGUCAUUUCGGGCAA